GAACUUAGGGCUGCUUGUGGCUGGGCACUCGCGCAGAGGCCGGCCCGACGAGCCAUGGUUGCUGGGAGCGACGCGGGGCGGGCCCUGGGGGUCCUCAGCGUGGUCUGCCUGCUGCACUGCUUUGGUUUCAUCAGCUGUUUUUCCCAACAAAUAUAUGGUGUUGUGUAUGGGAAUGUAACUUUCCAUGUACCAAGCAAUGUGCCUUUAAAAGAGGUCCUAUGGAAAAAACAAAAGGAUAAAGUUGCAGAACUGGAAAAUUCUGAAUUCAGAGCUUUCUCAUCUUUUAAAAAUAGGGUUUAUUUAGACACUGUGUCAGGUAGCCUCACUAUCUACAACUUAACAUCAUCAGAUGAAGAUGAGUAUGAAAUGGAAUCGCCAAAUAUUACUGAUACCAUGAAGUUCUUUCUUUAUGUGCUUGAGUCUCUUCCAUCUCCCACACUAACUUGUGCAUUGACUAAUGGAAGCAUUGAAGUCCAAUGCAUGAUACCAGAGCAUUACAACAGCCAUCGAGGACUUAUAAUGUACUCAUGGGAUUGUCCUAUGGAGCAAUGUAAACGUAACUCAACCAGUAUAUAUUUUAAGAUGGAAAAUGAUCUUCCACAAAAAAUACAGUGUACUCUUAGCAAUCCAUUAUUUAAUACAACAUCAUCAAUCAUUUUGACAACCUGUAUCCCAAGCAGCGGUCAUUCAAGACACAGAUAUGCACUUAUACCCAUACCAUUAGCAGUAAUUACAACAUGUAUUGUGCUGUAUAUGAAUGGUAUUCUGAAAUGUGACAGAAAACCAGACAGAACCAAGUAAGUACACUGCAGGCUGUGCACUCUGUGCCAGAACAACAGCAGCCCUGCUGUAGAUGCCCAUUACUUGGGAAGCCAGAUUGUACUCAUCUGUUGGUUGCCUUGUACAGUAAUAAGAAGUAACAUCAGCAGAUAUACUAACCAUAGUGUAUUAAGUACCAACUGUGUGCCAUGCACUGCACUAGCCACUCUCUGCAUAUCGUUUCCUGGAACCCUCUCAAUGAGCCUUGCAGGAGGAGUAUCAUACCCCUUGCUUAGAGACAGCGCAUAUGAGAUUCAUAGAAGUCAAGUGAGAUAUCAAAGUCACGUUGCUAGUAAGUGAUGGGCUGGGAUUUAAAUCUAGGUCUUUGGACUCCAAGAGUUAUACUGUUAACCACUACAAUACACUCCCUCCACCUCCCAUCCCAGAAAAAGUUGGAUCAGGGAUAGGGUUCACUUCAGGAGCCAGGGUCAGAGCUGGGCCUGUAGUCACAUAUAAAAGAUAGGACACAAACACAAUUAGCAGCAGUGUUGGUUUAAUAAACCGCCGUA